ACUCGCUCGCGCCGUCCGCAGCGGAGCGGGCAGCGGCCAAGUCAGGGCCGUCCGGGGGCGCGGCCGGCGAUGCCCGCAGCCCCCGCCGCGCCCCGCCGGGCCUGCUGAGCCGCCCCCGGGCCGGGGUCGCGCCGGGCCGGGCCGCGCCCGGGGCGGGGCGGCGCUGCCUGCAUGACCCUCCGGCGGCGCGGGGAGAAGGCGACCAUCAGCAUCCAGGAGCAUAUGGCCAUCGACGUGUGCCCCGGCCCCAUCCGUCCCAUCAAGCAGAUCUCCGACUACUUCCCCCGCUUCCCGCGGGGCCUGCCCCCGGACGCCGGGCCCCGAGCCGCUGCACCCCCGGACGCCCCCGCGCGCCCGGCUGUGGCCGGUGCCGGCCGCCGCAGCCCCUCCGACGGCGCCCGCGAGGACGACGAGGAUGUGGACCAGCUCUUCGGAGCCUACGGCUCCAGCCCGGGCCCCAGCCCGGGUCCCAGCCCCGCGCGGCCGCCAGCCAAGCCGCCGGAGGACGAGCCGGACGCCGACGGCUACGAGUCGGACGACUGCACUGCCCUGGGCACGCUGGACUUCAGCCUGCUGUAUGACCAGGAGAACAACGCCCUCCACUGCACCAUCACCAAGGCCAAGGGCCUGAAGCCAAUGGACCACAAUGGGCUGGCAGACCCCUACGUCAAGCUGCACCUGCUGCCAGGAGCCAGUAAGGCAAAUAAGCUCAGAACAAAAACUCUCCGUAACACUCUGAACCCCACAUGGAACGAGACCCUCACUUACUACGGGAUCACAGAUGAAGACAUGAUCCGCAAGACCCUGCGGAUCUCUGUGUGUGACGAGGACAAAUUCCGGCACAAUGAGUUCAUCGGGGAGACACGUGUGCCCCUGAAGAAGCUGAAACCCAACCACACCAAGACCUUCAGCAUCUGCCUGGAGAAGCAGCUGCCGGUGGACAAGACUGAAGACAAGUCCCUGGAGGAGCGGGGCCGCAUCCUCAUCUCCCUCAAGUACAGCUCACAGAAGCAAGGCCUGCUGGUAGGCAUCGUGCGGUGCGCCCACCUGGCCGCCAUGGACGCCAACGGCUACUCGGACCCCUACGUGAAAACAUACCUGAGGCCAGAUGUGGACAAGAAAUCCAAACAUAAGACAGCGGUGAAGAAAAAAACCCUGAACCCGGAGUUUAAUGAGGAGUUCUGUUACGAGAUCAAGCAUGGGGACCUGGCCAAGAAGUCCCUGGAGGUCACCGUUUGGGAUUACGACAUUGGAAAAUCCAACGAUUUCAUUGGUGGUGUGGUUCUGGGCAUCCACGCCAAGGGGGAGCGCCUGAAGCACUGGUUUGACUGCCUGAAGAACAAGGACAAGCGCAUCGAGCGCUGGCACACGCUCACCAGCGAGCUCCCAGGGGCUGUGCUCAGCGACUGACGCCCACCCGCCACUGCUACCCCUGCCGCCACCUGCGCCCAGCACGGCCGGCCCCGGGCUUCCCCAGCAGCCACCAAGGCCUGUGGCCCCCACACUGGGGGAGAUCCAGAACCCCUGCUUGGACACAGAGCCACUGCAGUCCCCGCUCGGAGGAUGUGGAGGGCUCAGCCACUCUGGGACGGGGAGGGCAAGGAGCUGGGGUGGGGGGCUCUCAGCUCUCUGGGGCCCAAGAGGCCGGUGGUGGAAAGAGACCUCAGCACCUGCCCAGGGGAAGGGGACACGCCCAUCUGGGAGCAAAGACCCUUCUAGAGGCCAGCCCCGGCUGAGAGGACAGGAGUGUGGGGGCGCCUUGGCGGACAGUGGGAACAGAGGAGGGAGGUGGUGAGCAGACAGACAGGUGGAGGAUGGGACCUUGAAGACUGGCUGCUCCAGCCCAAGAAAGCCUAACUGCAUCCCUCAUCUCCUUCGCUGCUGGACAGAUGGAAGAAGCGGGCCUGCCGGCCGAAAGUCUGCCAGAGUUCCCGGAGGCUCCUGAUGAUGGGUAAAUUGGCACAUGCUUCACUCAAUGAUUCCACAAGCCCUGGGGGUGAAUGAGACACAGGGCCUGCCCUCAGGGAGUUCCCAUCUAGUCAGGAAGCUGGGAACAAACCAUUCCAACUGGGGUGAGAAAUACCAAGACCAGCUUGGCCAGUCUGCAAGUACCGUGGGCUCUGCUGACUCUGCCGGGAGGUCAGGGACGGCUUCCUGGAGGAGGCGGUGCUUCCGUAAGGCCUUGGAGGGUGAGUGAGGGCUUCUAAAAGCAGUCCAGGCAGUGGGAGUGGUCUAAAACGCCUGGAGAGAGAAAGCCAAUGGGGCCGGGGUGCUGUGGACCCAGGGUCUCCUCUCCAGGGGAGGGUUUGUUAGGAAGGUGUGAGGCUCGAGGCAGGAGGUGGGGGACGUGAUGGAAACACCAUGGAGAAACUGGUGUAGGCUCAAGUUCAGACCUCAGACCCAAGUCUCCCACUCUGAUCUCUUUCUACUCCUGAGGGACCUCAAGGACGGAGCCCGCCCCUCCUCCUUCCUGGCAUAAGCAUCAGGUCAGCUGCAGUGGAGAAAAGGGUCCCUUGUGCUUGGGAAAAAAAGCAAGCAUUCCUACACGUCCUGACUCUGCCCUUUCCCCUCCCCUCCACUCCAUGGCUCACACUGGGGGCCUCCGGGUGCUUGCUCGUGGCAUCUUGGUCCCACUACCGCCACAGAUGUCCCUUUUGGGAGUAAUCAGUGGCCGUCCAGGGCCUUGUCUCUGGGGAGGCCUGUGGGGCCAGCUCCACCCUCCAGGAGCUGAGCAAGAAUCACCCUGGCUGGUGGGCCUGUCUGCUCCCCUGAGUGAGACUCCCCAGGAGGCUUGAGAGUAUCUGAAUCUUGGGGCCCAUGCCUGAAGCCCACAAACUUUCUCUGCCUACCAAGGGCCCCUCAGGAACGCUGGGUGAACAAAUGCAGAGCCAAGGAGUUGCACAGCCAGAGUCCCAGUGUGCUCAGCCCAUCAGUGUGUGAUGGAAACAGGCCCAGAGAGGUCAGGUGACCUGCCCAGGGCCUUCCAGGCCCCACACAGCUGGAACCAGGAUCCACAGCCCCCAGCCCAGAGUGCUGGACACCACGCUUCAGGGGAAUUGGCGUGCUGAGCUCACACCAGAGAGGUCCUGCUAGCUGCCAGCCUGGGGCUCCCCCGCCUGCUGCCCACCCCUUCAACACCGAUAGAGGGACUCACAGGCACGACGGUGGGACCUUCCACUGCAGACACAAAGCACACCACCACCUGAGGUCCAGGGUUAUGAUUUGAAUCCUACCAAGUGCCCAUCAGGCCUUUCCCAGGUUGCGGGGAAAACAGGACCCCAGCCCCCACACAGUCCCUGGCCACCUGCUGCUCCUGGAGACUUGUCUCCCUGCCUUUAGGAAGGGUUUUUGUGUGAAGGUUUUUGCAUGCACUGGUCUGAACGCAUGUUCACAGCCCUGCAAGGUGGGUUUGAUUCUCAUCCCCAUCUUGCAGGUGAAACAGGUUCCCAGAGUCUGAGUAGUUUGCCAAGGCCACACAGCCAGGAAGGGGUGAACCAGGACUCAAACCCAGGUCCUCUGACUGCCGCUUUCUCUCUCUGGGGGUCGGUACCCCCAGUCCCUUCCCUCUUGGUCUGUCGGAGACUCAGCAGAGACACCAGGUGAAGGCUCAGUAAGCUCAGGUGCAUGAUGGAGACCUGGGGUCUUGUCACUGUCCUGCCACCUCAUCCGCUGGCUUUGAAACCAUCCGUGCUACUUCAGGCUUCCCCAGAGGUGUCUAACCUGGCCCCAAAACUCAGCCACCCCACCCUAGCCUCUGGGGGCUGAGGCAAGGGCUCCUCUUUUCUCCACACAGAAUGGGCACCCUCUGGGGGCCUAAGGUAAGAGGUGGUCUAUUUCUAAAAGGCCUGGUGUCUAGUUAAGCUCUGGGUAUCUUCUUAGCUUUGCUUUUUUGGGGGUCUCAUUCAGAGAGGAGAUUUGACAGCCUCUCUGAAGACACAGAAGUGAAUGGCAAAGCGAGAAGAGGCUGUACCCCCCACCUACCAUGACUUCCUUAUUAGGCACAUGGGGAAUGUGAGGCCCAGUGGGUGAAAGGGGCCUGAAGGGGCACAGCUGGGACAAGAACCCAGAACUCCAGCCCCCCAGUCCAGGGCCCUCUACUGCCCAGGCUGUGCAAAUGGGGCUGGGACCGAAAGAUGGGGACAGUCAGGCUGGGAGGCGGGCUUACUGGCCAGCCAGCCCAGGGGCAGCACAGGCACUCGGGCAGGAACUCCCCAGGAAGUUUGGAUCCUUCCUUCCCUAGGAUCUCAGCACCCUUUUAGAUCCCGUGCAGAUUGUCUUUCUGUUAAAGCGUUUUGAGGCACGAUGGCUCACGCCUGUAAUUGCAGCACUUUGGGAGGCCGAGGCUGGCGGAUCACCUGAGGUCAGGAGUUCGAAACCCGCCUGGCCAACAGGGCGAAACCCCAUCUCUACUAAAAAUACAAAAAUUAGCCGGGUGUGGUGGCGCACGCCUGUAGUCCCAGCUACUCAGGGAGGCUGAGGCACGAGAAUCGCUUGAACCCGGGAGGUGAAGGCUGCAGUGAGCCAAGAUCGCGGCACUGCACUCCAGCCUGGGCGACAGAGCAAGACUCCGUCUCAGAAAAAAAACAAACAAACAACGCUUUGAGAAGCUGCAGAAGCGGCUCUGCCUUUGACCCCGAAUGGGCAUCUUUACUCGGGUCCAUCAUCCCCACAAAGACAGGAAAUCUGAUGCCAAAAAAAAAAAGUCAUUCCAGGUGUCAGUAACCAGGCGCUGCCUCCAGCGCCGCCCCGCCCGCCGCCCCGCCCGCCGCCCCGCCCGCCGCCUGCGCCAAUCCCCGACGGGCCCGUCUUCCAGCCCCGAAGCGGUCACCUCCUGACCUCUAGUGGCGAGCGCGGGGAACUGCGCCCCGGCCCGUCCGCCCGCCGAGCCCGGGCCGUGCAUGCCGAGCCCGUUGUUCCUUCGCAAACCGAGUGAACCUCCCGAUGCAUGGACUCUGGCUGUCGUCGACGCAGACUCUCGUGCACUGCUUAACCCCGUUUUGCUGCCAUGUGACGGCUGCAGACACUGUCCUCAAACUGCAGUCCCACAGACAAGUUUUGUAUUUUGGUCUGACCUACCCGAAGGUGUCCUUUUUAAGUCUUAUUUGUUAAUAUUUAUAAUGACAUAUAAUCCAAAGUAAAUGGAAACGUCAUAUUGCGAUCUCAUUGCCUUGGCGAGACUCUCACCUUUUAAUAGAUUUGAAGGGGUGGGGGCGGUGGCUCACGCCUGUAAGUCCUAGCACUUUUGGAGGUCGAGGUGGGAGAAUUGCUUGAGGCCUGGAGUUCGAGACCAGCCUGGUCAACAUGGAGAAACCACGCCUCUACACACACAGAGACACACACAAUGACAAUUAGCCUAGCGUGGUGGCACACACCUGUAGCCCCAGCUUUUCAGGAGGCUGAGGUAGGAGGAGGAGGAUCGCUUGAGCCUGGAAAGUGGGGAUUGCAGUGAGCCGAGAUCACGCCACCGCACUCCAGCCUGGGCAACAGAGGGAGACCUUGUCAAAAAAAAAAAAAAAAGAUUUGGAAGGGUAGGAGGGGAGGGUGGAAAGACGGAGGAAAAGGCAACUGAAACCUACUCCGGAUAUAGUCUUGUUACUCUUCACCAGGGACCCAUUUGAGGUAGGCCCUCAAGUUACAGAUGGGGAAACUAAGGCCCAGAGAGGUUAAAAUACUUUUACAGAAUCACACGGCUGGUCGAUGGCAGAAGCAGGAUUCAAACUGAGGCAGCCCAAGACAUUUUGCACCAGGACCUGUCGACCAUGCUGUUGUCCACUCAUCCAACAAACAGCCGUGGAGUAUUGACUAACGCCAGCCCGUCUGAGGCUCCAAGAGUCUUACGUUUUGGAAGGUAAUUUAAGACAUGUACUGCUUAGGUUUGGAGGGAAAAAAAUAAACCUUCCUAACCACAGAUUAGUGUAUUAGGACUAGUAGCAAUCCCCACACUUUAUAUUUUCAUUCCACCUUGUUAGAAAAUGUUGAUCAAUUGUUGAAUACAGUUUAUUGUACAUCAUUCUUUAGGUCAGAAAUUUCUCGAGAUAAAAGCCUUUGCUUUCUAACAUCGA